UUGUAUUCAUCUGUUGCUCAACCAUGGAUUUAUCCAUUCAUGAAAUUUAUUGAUGUACUACCAUGUUCUGGGUACUGUUGGCCUACAGUGAUAUACAAAGGAGGUUUCUGAAUCUAAAAAUGGCAAGUAUCCUAACUGAGAUGUUAGCAGAAUUCAGAGAAAAGAAAGAUUAUUUCCAAGGUUGGAGGAAUUGGGGAUGUAAGAAAAGUCUAAGAGAGAAGGUGUCAAAUAUGGUACCUGGUAUAUAUAGGAGCUACUUAAACAGUAUUUACUCCAUGAAUGAAUGAUGAAGGAACAAAUGAAAGAGAAGUAUCCUUUGGCCUUGCAAAGUGAGUAGGUUGGCAAUGCCAGACCAAAGGCAACCAUGUGAACAAAGGAAGACAGAAAAUUCAAGGCAAAGUUAGGGAAUGGAGAGCAACUCAGUCUAACUGGAUCAGGGAUGGGUGUUUUAAAAAUAGAGGGCAUCAAACUCUAAAGAAUUUGAAUCUUAUUUGUGUCAUAGGAAGCCAUUGAGAGUUUCAGAGAGGAUGGGGUGACCUGGUCAGAUCUGUGCUUUACGAAGACUUGGCUGGCAACAACUGGUAGGCUAGGAGGGAUGGAUAGAUUCCAGAAUCACAGGGGCUGGUACUGAGACUAAUGGAAUCAGCGAGCCUGAAUCUGCUGUGACUCUCUACUGCUUGAACAAUAUCCUCAGAAAAAUGAGCCGAGUGCCAUUGUUUUUAUCUGAUAGAACUGUUCUCGAUAUGGCCUGUAGAAAAUGUCAACCAAAUACUGUGGCAGGACAAAAUCAGUCAUGAAAUCAGACUACAAAAAAUUGCUCUCAAACAGUAAAGUUUGAGGUGAAGUAGCUCAUGAGGAAAAAAAAUCAAUGUAGUAAAAAUUAACACAGAAAUCAAAUCCUCUGCAAUCUAUUGUGCUUAAUUUUCAACAAUCUUAAGUGUUUCUGGGAGAGUACUUUGUAAGUUGAUGUUUUCUUUUUCUUUUUCCUCCUUUGAAAAGCUAUACACUGUGUAUGCCGUUUAUCCUUUUUCUGGCGCUUGUAACACAAAUUAUGAUUCCAUCCAGAUUAGCCCUAAGGUAUUUCACUUUCACUUCCUUUGAGAACUAUUUCUUUCUUUGUAAAAUAUACAAUUAAAAUAAUGAUAAUAGAAAACAGUCCAGAUUUUUAUGAACAGUCUUAUAAAUCCCAGGAUUCUGACUUUUUAAUAAUUUUCACCAUUGACUAAUACAUUUACAUAUGUUCUUAGUAAUGAAAGCACUACUUGAAUGACUAUAUAUACAUACAUAUUUAAUUCUUCUUAACACACAAAUACACAAAUAUCCAUAUCAUUAAAGUUUUUAUGCAGUGGGGAGAAUUAAAUGCAUAACACUCUUUUCUUCUCCCUCUACACUUUAUAUUCAGAAAUAGCUCAUAAAUAAGAUACAAGAAAGAAAGAUAGAAAUCAAAAGAUCAAAUUUAUUGUUGAUCAAGCUUUUUGGAAAAUGAAGCUUGGCAUUUGCAGCUAAACAGGCUUGAUUAUAUUUUGGUUCUUCCUCACUAUACAAGGAAGUGAUGGUCCACCCAAGGAAAUGAUUGUGUCUUCAGAGCACACACCCCUUCCCAGGAGGAUCAGUGUUGCCUCUGGUGCAGAGCUGAUAGAGAAGAGAAUCCUGCACUGCGGCCCCUUUCUCAAGAUUAGUCCACCAAUUGGAGUAACACAGCUCAGUGCCUGUCAGAUCACUGUUGCCCACAGUUAGAUAAGUUAACAUUUCUUCUUUGUGGAGAGGCAAAGGAGGAGGUGAGCAUGAGGUUGAGGGAGAACUAAUGGUGUUAUCUAUGGAAAGUACUUUCAUCUAGAUACACAAAACCAGUGGAAAGGAGGUUCCCCUCUAACAUGCUUAUACGAACACACACACAAAUGUCUUCAAGCCUAUGUAAAUAUUUCUGACUAUGAUUUUGCUAUAUGUAACUGAUUUUAAUAACUAGUACUUUCAGUGUUGAACAUUGGAUAUAAUCAAAUGCGUGUAUUAUAUACACUCAAGAAUGCAGAUAUCUAAGCCAUAUUUCAAAAAAUUAUUAAUUUCUAACAAAACAUUAAUUCAGAAAAGCAAUACAUUUAGUUUAAAAGUCCUCAUGACCAUAUUAAAUGUGAAAACAUGGAAUUAUUUCUGAAAUUCUACUGGAGCUGAUAUCAUAGCACAUAAAGCAACAAACUGAAACGCCUAGGUUCACUAGCAUAAUCCUGAUACUGACAUUAUAUUUAAAAAAAUUUGUACUCAUAUCUUUGUGGAUGUUCUUGGAUGACUUCUUUCCUUAAGGAUUUUGUUUACAACAAAAUAGUGAUUAUUAAGUUUUGCAAAGUGUCAAAGAAAGGUGGUGACAUAUUGGCUGAUUGUGAAAAUGUGAUAAAGAUGUCGUGCUGAGUAGGUGAACUGGUGGCCUCAGUGAGGACAGAGUAGAGAGCAGAAGGGGAUGUCAUUGAACUUCCAAACUCAGUAAAUUUCAGUGAUUUUCACUGAAACCAUCCUAAAAUUUCUUUUGAAUCUUUUAUAGUUUUAAGCAAAAUAUUUAGAUUAAGUCAGAUUCACACUUAAAUCCAAUAAUCUGUUAUCCAACAUCAAUUACUCAAUACAGAUGACUGGGCAGUGAAGCAAACUUACAUAACACCAGGCAAGGAAGAAAAGAACAUAAUAUCCUUUGCCUCUUUCUGCUGAUAGUCCAUGCUCCCAAGGGCAUUGUACAUAUCCUGAUAUUGCAAAAGAUACAACAGCAAGCCUGAGGGGAUUAGAAUUAUAUGAUUAGCACUUCUAAUUCUCAGGGUAGUUCUCUAUCUUCCUCCCUCCCCAGUACUGCCCAUCAUAUGCCAGUGUAUAUAUCUCUAUUUCCAGAGAGUAUACUUUGAUAGUGAAUUAUUUUAAAAAACACAUCUUAUUUCCUAUGUAUAAUUUCCAAUAAAAUCUUUAGAAAUCCAGAGUUUGUGAUUGGUCAUAGCAGAGAGAAUUUUGUUUGAUUUUGGAUUUUAAGUCUUUAGAAAAACAAAUUGGAGUGCAAGAAAAGUGAAAAAAAAAACUAAUUGAAUAAAAUGUAAAUGUUUGGAUGAAAUGGCUUACUAGUCUAAUUUGGUGAUAACUGACUACCCAAGAUAGCCUGCCAUGUUAGUAAUUGGGGAGGGAAACUUUUCAUUUCAAAUGACAGGUGAAUACCAUUUUCAGUGGUUAGCUUUUGAUUACAUGUCAUGUUUGUAGUGGUCUAUUGAAUUUUUAAACUGCUGUAGUCUGAUUGUGUUUGUGAAGUCUCUGUUCACUCAAAAGAAAGGAAGUGCCUACUAUAACCUCUUCAAUGCCAAAUAAAACCCCCUAGAUAAGCUUGGCCCAUACUAUGACUAUGAAAGAACUUCUACCUGGAGAUGAUGUCACAAAUUAGAGAGCUGGUUGCCUGGCCACUUAUCAGGGGAUAUGGCCUUGAAUUACACAGGCAUGUUGAAAUAGAUAUUAGACUCUGGAAUUUGGGAAAUGACAUUGUCUCCAAUAUUCAUUUUCUUGGCCUCUAGGUACCUUCAAACUAAAUGGACUCCAUUAAGGAUGAAAGUAUUGCCUUAGUAGAACUCUCAGACUUCCAUUUUCUCUCUGGAAGGCUUGUUUUGCAUACGCAUAUGUUGCACAACAUAUGGAUUUUUGAGUUGUUGGAGUAUAAAUUCUAAAUGUAUAUAAAUUUAUUAUUGUUUAAAGCUGAAUCAUUCAAGGUUUCUAAUAUAAAGUCUGAUUUUGUGUUCUACUGGAUGGUAUUAAGUGGAUGAAUUGCUCAAUUGUUACGACUGCUUGGCAAUCCUGUUUCCCUUUCUGAUAUUGGAUACCUUCUUUUAAGAAAGUAUUUUUUAAGCUGAUGAUAAUCUUUUCUCCUACUUAUUGAGGGCUUAGUAUGUGCCAAUAAAAUGUCACUAUUAUUGUACCACAUUGGAGAUGAAAUUCAAAGAGGAAAGACAUGUGCUUGAUGUAAGCAGCUUAGCAAGGUCCAACUCAGGUCUUCCUGCUCUCAGUGGUGAUUCAGGACAGCCUCUUUAUCAAGCAACAUCCUUUUUUAUUAUUGUGAUUAGUUUACUAUUUUUAAUAAGGGAUGAAAUGGACCUAAUUAAAUCCAAUCGAUAAGAUAAGAGCCCUUACUUAGGACAAGAACUUCUAUUUUCCUGAUGCAACCAGGAUUUCUUGCUGCAACUUUCAUAUGAAAAAUCAGAGAAAUGUAGAGAACUUUUAUAAUUGUGAAGCUUUUAACAGGUAUUUCUGUUUCAUUAGAAUUAAGAUCCUGAUUAAUGAAGAGAGAUGAGAAAGUAUGUGCUUAAAUGAUGAACACUCUCUUAGGUAGUCUAUGGAAAGAAUGAUUGUUUCAGGAACAACCAUCCUCCUAGUUUAAGAGUAUAAAAAGAACGCCUACAUUUUAAAUGUUUUCCCUUAUACUCAUUAUUGGCACACUUUACUCAGGACUUAGUAGUCAGUUUUACCAUGUAUUCUAACUUCACCUUCACCUUUGUACUCUAAAAUUUCCUUGCAUUAGGAUCAAGUUUAGAGGUAUCCUUUUAUCUCAAAGUCAAUUCUACCAACUAUGUUUUCAGAGAGAAAUGUUAUCAUAAGCCUGAAAUCUUAUGCCAGAUAAUUAGAGGGGCUCUUAAUGCUGUUUUCUUUUUCCAGCAAAGUACUUUAAAUAAAUGCUUCAUAAAAGUAGUUCUUAUGUAAAUAAAAAAAAAUUAAGGCUCAGUUUAGACCUUCUUGGUUAAAAUAACCCGUUGGAGUUCAGAGGGCUUAUACACCACAAUGUUAAAUGCUCUAAAUACCAAAGUGCCAUCUUUCUGAAUUUUAUUGUUCUCACUGAAUCACUGUAUUAUCUUGAUACUUUCUAGCAUUUUCAGUGCAAUUAUUAAAACAGUUAUGGCCGCUCUAAAGGAAUGUAAUUGGAAAAGAAAGAUGGCCUGUACUGGAUGAAAUUUUUAAUUAAUCUUUCACUGUUAAAUUGUUCAAAAUUAAUCAAGUAUAUUGCCUAUAAGAAGGCAACUGCACUUUACAUACUUCAGUAUUAUCAUCACCAAGCCAUAUAUUAAAAGUUAAUUUCUGAUUUAAAAGUGUACCUUAACUGCAAAACCGUCAAUUCUAAGUAAUUCUAUUACUCCCCUCACCCCCAAAAAAUCUUAUAAAAACCAAAGGACAUGAUAAAGAGAGUGCUUUGUGCUUAAUGUUUUGAGAUUUUUUUUUUUUGGCAUGGACUUUGCAACAUCAAAUUAGGAUAUAUGAUUUCAUAAAAUAACUAAUCUGAAUUGGAGAAUACCAUUCAUUCACUCAUUGAUUCAGUCAUUCAUUCAUUUAUUUAACACAUCUAUGUUGAAAAAAGUGAUGUUUUAGACAAUGAGAAUAAUGACUGAAAUGCAAUAGCAAUUUUCUGACAUAUUAUGAGACAAUAAACAACUUAAAUUCUAAUCACGGCUGUAGAUAAAUAUCCUUGGGGAUAUUUGAGAAAAUUAUGAAAAGGUGGUGAUUCCCCCCCCCACCUUUUUGAAUUAUGCAGAUUAUAUUCUCCACUGGUUCUUGCUUUUUACCGCCCUAACAUAUCAGAGUGAUAAGAUACAACCCACCUGAUACACUUGGCCCCGAGGAAGUGCUUCUCAGAUAAAAGGAGGAGGUGACUUAUCCCUUUGCCAGAGCUGGGAAUGACUGAAAGAGUUCCUUGGCUGUCUGCCCAUUCCUAGGUUGAGAAUUAUCAGUAAAUGGGAUCAUAGGUAAUUACUGAGUAGGCCACAGAGAUAAUGUCUAAACACAUCUAACGCAAGGUCCUUAUGAUCCUAAUAGAGUCAGUGGAACUAAGUAAGUGUAGUUGAUUUUUUCCCCCAAUAAGUCAACUGGUUGUUGAUUUAAUUGAUUAAGUAGAUAUUUUCAUGCCACACAGACAUACUCUAGAUGUCAGCAUAAAAUAAAUAUAUUAUUUUGUUGGAUAUUUUUUAAGAUGUGAUAGUUGUGAUCAAGACCAUUUUAAGAUAAAUGUGUAACAGAUAUUUCUCAAAGCCAGAACAGCAUGAAAUGUUAUAUAUCCCUGAAUGCAAAAGUCAAGAGGUAUGUCUAAGACUUUUCUGCUUUGAUGUUAGAGCAGUCUUGAUCUUACCACCUGGCUUUCAGAGACUAUAAGAAGCUAUUUCAAAGAGGCAAAGAUGUAAAAAACAAAUGUGCUACUGUUCUUAGAAUCAAUGAAAUAAGGUUAUACCUUUUCCUGACAAUUUUCUAUGUUCUGAUACAUAUUAUAUUUUUAAACCUGCAUGCAAAACACAUAUAAUGCUACACAUUGAGAUGUUACUUAGGAAAGUCAUAUUAUAUGAAUUAAAUGGGGAACCCACUGAGAUGAUUAAGAUAUAUCUGUGGAAUUUAUAGACAUUAUUCAUCUACCAGAUAUUGCCUCUUUAGAAAGAGUAUCCUGGAAUGCCAGGUUUGAUUGAAUGACUUGAAAUUGGGUAAAAAUCUUUUCUGUACUGGGCUAGCCAUACAAUGAAGUCAGCUGACACAUGGGUAAAAUAGACAAGCUAUUUAAUGUCAUGAUCUGAGGAAGUUAAAAAAAGAGUUUUUAUUUCUUCCUGCCAUGGAUUAUCUCUGCCUUUCCUCUUUUUAAAAAUAGAAAUGCUUCUUUGAGAGUUAACACAUCAUACUUCUAACAACUUAUCAUGGGUUAGUUUUUUAUUGCUUUCUGUCCUGACUAGGCAUAUAGAAAGAAAAGUGCAGCAAACAAAAGGAUAACCCUGAAGAAAAACUUGAGCUGUUUCUCUGCUUUGUCUAAUCUCCUGUCAGGACAUCAUUUAUUACCCACAAUAUUCACUUGAGAAAACAACUUUGAGAAACCAGCAAAGAAAAAGCCAAAGGAUGAAGAUGAAGUCCUUCUAUAGUUCAAAUCGCUCAUGUCUGUGAUCUUCAAAAUGUGACAUUGGACAAUCAAUUUAAAUGCUCUUUUUUAAAAGAUAGACUGUUGUAUUGAUUAUUAUUUCAUGCUAUCUAAAAGUUUCCAAAAUAUUUUGUCUUGUUGUAAAGAGAGAACCAGAUUAAAACAAUCACGUGUCAGUUUGUUUUCUAAAUAUUCAUAUAUUCUCCUCCCUUUCUGAAUGACAGAGCCGUUGACCAACAGCUGUUUCUAUUAUGUAGUUUGGGAUAUGCUUCUUUCGUUUGUUUACCCUAUUAAUGUGAGGAUUUCUAAUGUUUCAUCCUUCAGACAAGGAACUGGUCCUGAUGGCCUAGCUGCUACCUAUAUUUUCCUGGCUUCUUUUGUAUGGUAUUAAAUAUGAUUUAGAGGUUUCUUCAAAUUGUAUUUUCAUUAAAGGAAAAAACCAAGCAUGUAAGAGCCAGACAGUUUUAUAAGAAGAGUAGAAUAUCAUGGUGUAAGGGGUUAUGCUGUGCUUCCGUUUUAUGUAUAAUUAAGCAAUUCAAGCAAAUCAAGAUAAUUUAUCUUAGCAACUAGAUGAUUAUUUUUCUCCUUUUGAAUAGGAGCUGUCUUUUAUUUUGUUUAAAAAUGCAUCCUUACCUUCUGUUUUGGAACAGAAUAGAAGCAUUUAAAAAGAUAGAAUUUCGUAUUGUUGAAAGAAAUGUGAGACAAAGCUGACAACCCGUUCAUAAGGCCCUUUCACCCCAUCUCUAGGCAUGGUGACAUUGGUACAGACAGGGUUUGUCACUCAUAAAUUUACAGCUUAUUCCAGUCUCUUCAUAAAUUGACUAAAUUUUUUGAAAGAAAAAAAAUAUAGAUGUAUAAAAUACCCAGUUAUAGGUUGUGUUCUAUUUAGCCCUUGAUUGAAACGUAUUGCUCCUUAGUAUCUUUUAGCUAUGAAAAUUAUAAUAUGGAACAGAGAUUAGAAUGAAAUUAUCAUGGCUAGAAGGCAUUUACUCAGUGGUGGCAACCACAUAAACCUGGGUCCUGAGAAUGAUGAUAAUACAUUAGGUUCUGCAUGCCCGAUAUUAUUGCCGUACAUUAUGUAUGUUUCAUUUAUACUAUUUCGCACACACCAGCAACGCUGACAGAUAGGUAAUUACUCUCUGCGCCAAUGAACAGUUAUCAGCACCACCGCUGUUUAUUGCUGGAAUGAAGCGCGCUUGUCAGUCAAGGUCACUUGUUUGUGUGUCCUCUUCAAUAGUUCCUUCACAGUUGUUGAACUUUGCACACAGUUCUUAUUGCAGGGUUCCUGGAGGUUACUUUACUACAUAAUGUGUUUCUGGUGUUAUCAAAGUCACUUGUAUUUAUCACUUUAAUUGAUAAACAACGAAGUCACAGGAAGCAGAACUGAAGAUGUGAAAAAACAUAUUUUGCUAGUCAGCUGAUCCCAGUAGGUUUUCAGUAAUGAAUGACCUCAAGAAGAUGCAUUCAGCACAGACCCUUUCAGGUUGUGAUACGCUGCCAGCCUAAGCUAGUGAAAUCUCAUUUUAUAACAUUAACCUUAAUUUCAGCUGCUGAUGGAUACUGACACAAUUUCAUAACUACUAUAGAGUUAAUGUUUUUACCCUCUAGAAGUGUUUUUCUUUGUUCAUUUCUUGUGCAGUGCAGAGGUUAUUUUCAUGCUUAGUAUAGUUCUAUAAUGGGCUAAGUCCAUUUGGUUUGACUUAAAACCAGUCAUGUUUAUUUGUUAGAUAUGUGCCAUUAAAGCCUCCCCUUCCCAUAAAAAAUAUUAUCAGUCUAAUGCUGGUUCUCCUCAUUGUGUUAAAGCACCGGUCGUGUUCCAAAAUGAACAUUGCAUGGUGCAUUUUUUAGAGUAAAAAUAAAUUCAAUGCCAUUGUGUCGAUCCCAUGCAGCCUGUAAUUUCAUCUGUUAUAAAAUAAAGAGAAUGGUUGGUCUUUUUAUUUUUGUUUGUUAGCUACAGUGCUUUAUUAGAAACUGGAAUAACCUCUGUGAUAUAAUAAUUUAUCUAGUCAAGAUAACUGGAGUUAUUUCCUUAAGCCUGUGAUCAGCUUGAGUUUGUGUGUUGGGAGGUUUAUACUGCCGUUGCUUAUUACCAAAGAAACAGUUAAAAAGGAUUUAUGGUAGUGCCCGUUAUGUGUGUGUCUGGAAUUUUUGUGUAUUUAACUUCUCUCCUUGCCUAUCUCUGUUUUUUCCUCUCUUAACAUUAUCGUCAAAUAGAGAGACUAUCUAUACCUACAAUUAAAUGCAAAUUUUAUUCAGGCAUUUAAGCAGAAUCACAUUCAUUCAUUAAACCAAAUGAUUCUUUUAUUUGAAAAAAUAUAUCAGCACAUGGUAAUAUCACACCCUGCUUACAAGGGCCUCUAGUUCUCUGUCAGUGCAAAAGUUUACUAUUUCAUUAUUAAAGGAUUAAACUACAGCAAAAGCUGCCUGGUGACCAUGAAUGUUUUAGUUAAUUUGAUUAUGCCCAUAAAGAAAGAGUUUAAUUCCAUAGCAGCCAGUGGGUCUUAUACCUGGCAGUGUGGUUCCAAUGCAUUACGGGCAUGAUCUUAUCCUGGGAGAGACUGAAAUUGCCAUUUGGGUGAAGUGUGGAGGAAGAGAUGAGAACUGGGUUCACUGGUGAACCCAGGUUAACACCAUGCCUCGACGUUUUCAAAAUGCUUCCUUUUCUUAGUUCUUAGUUACCAGAGUGUUACAAAGAAAGGGUUUUGAUCUCAUGUAGAUAGCAUAGCAUUAAUUACCCUGACACUAAUUAAACUGCAUCAAACAAAUACCACCGUGUUCCUCAGGGGGACAACAGAAGGCAGUUUAAAAUAAUUACUGGAGCUUCAUGCAUGUGUGAAGUUUUCAUUACUCUUAGGACACAAGCAAAAAAGAUUUGAUAUCAUUAAAAUAGCCACCUUUUAGUGAUUGCAACAACAACAACAACAACAACAAAAAGUGACUAAAAUUUCCUUGGAGCAUAUUGAUGUCUAAAUAGUGGUGGCUUCAGUUCUUCAGAAUGGUAACUUUUCCUUAAGAAUUGGAAGUGUGUGAAGCAGGAACAGGUGUUCCAGUCACAUUCUGGUAUGAUUAUGUAUUAGCUUAUGUUUGUCAGACCAUUUCAUUAACCACCCACUGCUAUCACAUAUACAUAUACUUUGUUCUUUCUGAACCAUGAAAUGAAAUGCAUAUAUCUUCACUAAUGCUUGCUAUCAAUGUAAAUGAGAAAAAGAGGCUUAUUACCAAUCACGACUCCCAUGAAGUCCACACCUCUGUACACUUACAGGUAAUAAACAUCUUUUUUGUAAGUAGAACAAAAGAUAUAUUGAGUUCUGCCUAUAAUAAGAGAUAGUGAUCUUGUCCUACUUUUUUGUCCUAAUAGAUGGUACUUCCCAUACAUAGUUUGACACAAUGCUAUGGGAAGCAAGCUUCUCUCAAAACUGGAAGUGCUUGUUAUUUUUGAGAUCUGACAUCAUUCUGGACAUAAGCAAACUUUUCUGGUCACAGAUAAUGGACCUUUUGUGCCACUGGACAAGUGCAGUGAAUUAGUGGCCACCGUUACUAGGAUCAUAGAUGGUCCCUGUCCUGGUGGUUGUUAGAAAGGACUGAUGUCAAAAUUGCCAAAUGGAUGGUAUAAAUGAUUGACAGUGUUGCUGUGUUAGGGCCGGUUAUGGUGACUGUGGAAGUUGCUCAUGUUUGAUUGCUCUUUUAAGUGUGUGUGACUCUGCACAUGUGUGCUUGAUGUGUGUGCAUGGUGAAUUCUAUGCGUCGUCCCCACUGUCUGCUCAGUAUAUAUGCACACAGCACAUUCUACAGUUUUGUCCUCACAAGGUCACUUAUCCUAUUUAUCUCAGUGACAUAUGAGCAGUGGGACUCAAGUUGUCUGGGUUCUAGCACCAGGUGCCAGCCAUCCUCCCUGAAAAGGUGUUGGGAAUUAAAAUGGGAGAGUGGUCAUUUCCAGAUUGAUGCAACUCAUAUUUCAUUCAGUGAAUGACUCCUUGAAUGUGAUUAUGGAGUGGUUCUGUGUAUGCAGUACUGCAUAACAUAAGCCAUUUAUUUUUUUACUUCCUUCUGAAAGCAAUAAUUUAAGGGAAUUAUGCAUUAUGAGGGUUUUCCAGUAAUUUUUUUUAAAAUUAAAAUAAUGCUAGCUAUUUUAGGAAACCUGUUUAGGAAAAUAACACUGAAUUAGUGCUUUGCAGUUGUCACACUAAGCAAAAAAUGGAACAAAACUGAUUGUAGAAGAAUAAAAAAUUAAUCCAGUUGUAGAAAUUUGAUGUGUUCAAAAAUAUGCAAAAAAUAUACUUUUGUUCCUUUAUAGCCAGAUGGUUUGUCCUAUUUUAAGCUGAUAGUAACUUCAUACAUCUCUCUUGAAUGUCAUUGGUUUUAACUGGCAGACAGUAUCUACUAUUAGAAUUUUCCUUAUUCCUGGAUGAUCUAAAGUGUAUUUUUGGAACAUUUGGAUGAUCAUACUGUACACCAAGAAAAUUUUUUCAUUACACUUAGCUCAUACUCAAAAAAGUGUUUAUAUAAUUUUAAAAAAACCUCUAAAAAUGAACAGUUCUUUUGACAUGAUGUUGACAGAAGUCACUUUGAUGUAGUUUAGAGUCAUGAAUUUUCUAUCUGUUCCAUUUUUCCUGGGGCUCCAUCAACUCAGACAUCCUGAUCUGUCAUUUUUCAACUCUUUGUGAAGGCCUUGACAGAUAGAGGUUUUGACAAGUGCUGGACAUCAGCAGCAAUUUAGAAUAAGCAGUGUAUAUUUCUCCAGGUAAAGUGACAAAAUGUCUAAAAGUGUCAGAAGAACUAUGUGGCCUGCAAUCAUCUCUAAUACUAUAAAGCAAGCUUCCAUUUAAGUACUGUGUUGCAGCAUUGUAUGAUGGCUGAAAUUUAAAAUUCUGUCAGAACCUAUGAUUAGAGGGCAUCUGGCUUAUUUACAAGUGUUUGCAAUAUUAAGAACCUUAGGGUCACUAGAAAAAAAUCCUUUAAAUUUCUAAUGAGUGAAUGAUCAGGAUAAUCACAUAAUGUGAUAGGAGUCUUUAAAACUAUAACACACCAUUAUAUAUUUUUUUGUUUCUUCAGUACUAAUUUGGGUCAUUCUUUUUAAUGAAAACCUACUUCCUGUGCUGUCUUCAGAGUGUACAGUUCAGAGUUCAACUUAAGGGAACUUUCACUGGGUGCUAAUUAUAACAGGUCAUUCAGGUUUCAGAUGUGCCAGCAUUUUUCCUGGUUGACUCUUCUAUCAAUGACUAAGUAAUAACUGUAAAUAUCAUCUCGCAUAUUGAAUAUGUUGUCCUUUUCAUAUAAUUAUUUUGUGUCUGUAUUCACUCAAGAAACAGCUGUUAAAAGUUGAGUGGGAUGCAAAAUGGCACAGCCUGAAGAUGUUCUUACUCACUCAGCUAACUCCCUUUUGAUGUGAUACCUACUGGCAGGGUCGCGUGGUGAAUUCAACUUCUUUGACAGCCAUCAGCACUACUGACCAGUGGUUUUGGGUUUUCUAGUGAGGGGAAAGAGUAGGAAAGAAUUCCGUAGUUUAGUUUUUUUCCCCCCCCUGCUGCUGGAGCUAAAGCUUCUGCCAACAACUAUCUAAAUCAACACCAUGCCAACGUGAUCUGCAGACCAAAGGUCACUCCAACAUCUGGCCCCACUGUCUGCUUCUUUCAGGUUUGUCACUGGGCAGCAUCUGCUUAUGGAUUCUUUCUCAACCUCUCUUUGAUCUCUCUGACAGUAAAAAGAAGCUUCUAUCACCCAUCAUGUGUUAGGACUUUAAAAAAUAAAUUCGAAAGCAUGAGACAUUGGAAAACUGGUGGAAUUUUAUGUUUUUCACUCUUGUAUACGUUGAACAUUUUAUUUGAUACAAGGCCAUGGACUAAGGUGAUUCUACUCUUGAUUUCAAAAAGUAUUGUCGUAAUCAGUAAGUCCAGUCUGUGAAAAUAUCUGGUCUAUGUGAGCCCUGUCUUGUCUCUCUUGGUCAGGAUUUAAAAAAUGAAAACUGAAGAGCACAAACUGGUUUUGUUUUUGGUUUGUUUGGUUUGUAUUGACUCUGAAGAGUCCGUGGUGAUAGCUCUUGUCUGCUUUUCUGACAUUUCUAUCAGUGGUUGAGAUCUCAUGUAUUUUUCAUCCAUAGUGUGGAAUGUAGAGCACAGUUUGGGGAUGCUACAUAGUCUCUGGGUACAUAUUGGUGAACAUGGUCAGCCUUUUCGUGAAACGAAGCCCAACAGCCUGUUCUCCCUGGCAGCAGUGGCGUAUCUCCUAGAUAAGGCACAAAAACAGCCCCAUGCGCUAUUAGUUCUUCCUUCAUUCCUUCAGCCCUCCUCCCUCCAGGUGAGUUCUUAUUAUGUCCAACCUGGAGUUCAAAUUCAGCCAGCACAAAACGAAUGCUGACUCUGUGCCUGGCACUAUCCUAGGUGUUGGUUAUACAGAAAUGGACAAGACAGACACACGUCCUGUUCUCUCAGAGUUUACAGUCUGGAUUGACACAGCGGGAGGGGGGCUUACACAUUUUCAUGUCAUAAAAAACUGAAUGAGUCAGAAUGUGUUUGGCCUUCCCCAAGAAGUGGCAACCCAUUACUGUAUUUAUAUGUGAGUAUAAUUAUAAGAGUUCACAGCUAUGAUUGUAACACAAUUUUAGUUCUAGUCCAAAUCAAAUGCCAAAACUCUCAGGGGAAAAAUGAUAAUGCAUUCUCCAGCACCUAACACAGAACCUGCCAGGCAAUACACGUUGUGGAGAGAAUUUGUGAUUUUCUUCCAUUUUCAUUCAUUCUCCAAACAGAUUGGCAGUUUCUAUUUUCCUUCACCCUCCAGGAAACUAAAGCAGUAGAUAAAACCCUUUUUUUCCCCUGUGUGAUUUAACUUUGGCUAACUAAAACAAGAACUUGUGUUUGUAGCAUUUGCCACAAUUUCACAGCACUUUUACUGCUUUGUCAUCAUUUAUUUUUCACAAAAUUCCAGAAAUGUACAAGAAACCCAGAAUUGAGCUGUUAAGUCCACAGUGACUGAGAGAGCAUUCAGACCAGAAAUUUGCAUGUAUUUUUACAAUUAUUAGUUUUUAACAUCUCAUGUUCAUCUCAUAAAAGAAUUACCUAGGAACUUGUUCUGUCAGUUAACCAGUGCUUCAGAAAGUGCUUAAAUAAUUGAUGAAAUAUAAGAAAAAAAAAGUAAGCAAUAUGACACAAAGAAUGGGACUAUUUCGUAUGGAAAUCAGGCUAAAUACUUUACAGUCACAAAUCAAUGCUAAGAUGAAGACUGACAAAGCUAGCACUAUGUCUCCUUAGCCAUACAUAUUCCAAAAAGACUGGGGCUCAGAGUAGCUGGCUUCUCAUUUCCUUUCCUGCUGACUAGUUUAGUGACCAUGAACAAGUCAUUUGAGCUUCCUGGUUCUCAGGGUUUCAUUUUUCAUCUGCAAAAGAUGGUCUGAGGAUUAGGUGGUAAAAAUAAUAAUUUAUAUCUGAUUUUUUGCUUUGCAGUUUAUAGUUUCCACAUAUAUUAUCCCCUUUAACCAGAACUUUGUUUCAAUAUUUUAGGAAUCUGUAGUUUCAUUAUAAAGGCUAAAUGUUUGAUUUCCAAAAGUAUUGUCAUAAUCAAUAAGUUCAAUAUGUAAAAACAUCUGGUCUAAGUGAGUACCAUCUUGUCUGUCUUGGUCAGCAUUUAAAAAUAAGGCCUUCAGUGCAGGCAUCAGAUAAUAAUGACCCUGUAUGAUAACCUCAUACCUGCUUUGGAAAUUAUCUAACUGUGGAAAUCCAGUCCCCUAAAUGAUAAGUGCUUGUAUUGGUAAAGAAUAGUCAUGACCCUGUUAAUAAAUCUGUUGUUGGGUCUUCUUUGUUCUGGACAUUUAGCAUUACAAACUCAGAGGAAUGAAUUAAUGUCCAAUAAAUUAUAAGAAUUAUAACUGUUCUAUUUAUCAUAUACAUUUAGAUAAUUUAAGAAUAGAAUCUACAUUUUGCAUUUUUAAAUUUAUAUCUAAUUACAUCAUUUGAAGUACUUGAAAACAUUUUGCACAUCAAAAAAUUUUUCUUUUCUUUUAAAAGCAGCCAGAUUACAAAAUAGCCCUUUUUUUGUUAACCAACCUGAGAAUUUACAUAUAUUACUUUGACCACUAGAGGGAGUCUGCAUUGUCAGGAAUGCCAAGCCCAAGAGAACAUGAAACAGGCUGUUUUCGGGUGCUGAUGACACAUCCAUUGUCUGUCCACGAUAUCAUAUGCAUACAAAUUGCCAUAGUAAUCACAUUAACUGUCACUGGGUUCAUUAUUUUCCUUAAAAAAAAAAAAAAAAAAAAAAAAAAGGAAUUUGAUAACAUGUUUUAUUUUGUUCUUUUUAAAAAGUGCACAACUUUUAAAAGGUGACAAAAACUUACAAUGCUUCCUUAAAAUAACAGAGAUUUAGCAGUCUGAAGAACAUGGGGGAUUAAAUAACAUAAAUUAGUGAUAAUCUGAUCACUUCCAUUUUAGGGCUGGUUUUGUAAUCUGGAAAUGAACAUGUCCUCCUUCUCCCUCAGCCCGCCGCCCAAUGUAGGCAGCAGCUGUGCAGGGUUUUUGCAUCCUAACCUACUGAUGUACAUCGCCCCUAACCUGCAGGGACUUCCUUCCAGGGUGAGAGGGUAAUUGUGGCUCAUGUCCGGUCAGUCCUCAGACCUCUUCUGAGACUGCCAAACAAGUGGCUUUGCGUGUGUAUUUUUCACAGAGCCGGUUUAUAAAUGAGGAACUGAGCUGAAACCACCUGCUCGUUUCACCUCAGCUACCAAAAGCAGAGGGAGGGCAGGGACAGCCAUUCCUUUCUCAGCAUGGCUGAUUUUUAGUCAGCAGCAUAUAAUUGAAGGGUUCGAAUUGUUUUGAAUUUCAGAUUUUCAACAGGACCCUUGAGUUUUGCUUAAAUGUCUUAUCUUAUGCAUUAUUGACGUCAGAUUCAGUUCAUUUCUGGAUUGCCCACUUCUCGUUACCCAUGUACUCAGAAGUCAGGACAGAACGGGCAAUCAAAACUGCAGUUUGUUAUUACAGAUAUGUAUUUAUGUAUAACUUUUGUUCCUACAUUUUGAUACAGGUAGCUUUGAUAAUCUGGGAAACCAUUACAUUCCUCCCAGAUAAAACCUGCCUCAGAGUGGCCUAGCAUAGUGCUUCUCAAACUACACGCAGAGACAGACCACUUCCUUUAUUUCCUUCCAAUUUUUUUGGAUCAAUACUUCCACAAAAUACAGUAAAAAUAAAUGACUAGAAAUAAAAAACACUUGAAAUAUUAACUAAUUUUCUAUUAUUAUCUUCAACAGACAAAAUUAUUCUGUGAAAUUGCUGUAAGAGUUUCUAUGCUCUUCCUCUCCUUUCUGUCUCUCACUGUGGACCAGCACAGGCAGUCCCGAGGCCAGCAUUCUGACUUGCACUGGCCUCAUAGCACUCUCAUUUACCACCCUACCUCUGCACCUUUCAGACUCAUGCAGAGCUCCAACUUUAGCAGAAUUCCCCUGUUCUUCCUUAUCUAGAGCAAGGCCAGACUUGGAAGGUUUUGCUUCAGUACUGAACAUAGAGUGGAGGUAAACAGAAAAAGCCAUAUUUAAAAUUACAAAGCAGAGUUGGUGGCAGUGUUGGUUUAAUGAAAAUAAGGUUUCAAAUGUUUGACCCUGAGCAUGUAAUUAAAAGUUUAUUGCAGAUGAUAUUUUCUAAUCACCUCACUCUACAAGAGAUUCAAUAUUAAAUUAUUUCUUUUCUUAUGAAUUUGGGGCAGGAAUGAAGCAAUUAAAGGGGGUCUUCAUGUUCAUGAAAUAUUCAGUAGGUAGAGAAUCUGGAGAGCUUAGUAAAAUAAUAGGCUGAACACACUGCCUUAUUUUUCUUUCUUUUCAGUUGCCCUUUGAAAUAGAGCUGAUGGUAAUUUUGUCUUCCAAGCCUCAACGCGUAUUGAGGACAGAUUAGCUAAACACACUGGUCUGGGAAUCAAGAGACCUGGUUAUCAUCUUGUCACUACUUACUAGCCAGAUGGCCUUCAGCAAAUCACUUUAGACUUCAGUUUUCUCUUCUUAAAAUGGGAAGACUGUUACCUCUCUAAUUCCCUCACAGGCUUGGUUGCUAGGAAGAUCAAGUUAACUAGUCAGUGGGCUUUGGAGACCAGCAAACAAGUUACACACACACACGUAUAUAUGUGUAUGUGUAUAUAUUGCAUGGUUCUCCAUUUAUUUAAUCAUGUAUUUCUCUUGAAUGCUCUUGAAAUAUAUACCUUCUAAGUUCAUUGUUAAUCCAUUCCAUUUUAUGGUCCUUUCUCACCCUAUGCCUAGUCCACCCAUAACUUUAAGCACAUGGUUAUUUUUGUACUUCUUUUGAAAGGUAAAAGAUAAACUUAAAUAUACACAAUACAGUUUAUUAUUAGAAAUGUUAGAGGAAAGGAUCAUUUAAGUAUAAUCUACAAGGUUUCAUCUCACUUGCGCAGUGUUGUGAAGCAGAGGUAUGGUACUGAGCUAUGCUGUCUGGAUAAGAGGGAGCCUGGCCUCUGAAGGCUCAGUGUCAAGCCCCAUUGCUGCCUCCUUGCCAAAACACACACAAAGACACAUGCCUGUAUGCACAUAUGUGCACACAUAUACAUACCCGCACACACACACGGACGCACACAUAUAGAAAUGUAUACAUGUGCAUGCACACAUGCACACUUACACAAAUGUGCACACACAUCCCAAGUGCUUGACACUCAGUUGUCUCCCAAUAGCCAUGGCCAGACCUGCACAAUUUCUGCAUGACAGUACUCUGUCAUGCAGAUCAUGUCUGAACGACAUACUCUGGCUAGGCUCUGCAAGUGAAGAUAAUGGGACUUCCUUUGGAGAACAGUGAUUGCAAAUGAGACCACAAGGUCAUUGCCCUGAGAGCAAAGAAGCAGGAUGUCUUAAUGCUGGGACACUUGGCAAAGCCUAGUCCUGACCAGCCUCUUCAGUCCAUGAGGAGACAGCUUUGAAUGAUUUGACUCCAAAUAUGAAAUUCUGGAAAUAGAAAAUGGAAAAGCAUUUUUCACCCUAGUAAACUGGAACAUGUGGCUGGAAGAGUUACAUGUGGCUCGAGAACAGUUUGGAAGAAUUACAGAACCUCAUUCAUUCAUACAUACAUUCAAACAUUUAUAGAGCAUCUAUAAUGUACCAGGUCCAGUGCCUGGUACUGGGUAGACAGUAGCAAGAAAAAAUAAUCUGAGUAUCUGCUCUCAUAAAAAAUAUGGAUAAUUAUAAUACAGGUGUGGAAAUGACUCCAGGAGACUUUUCCCUCUUCUGCUGUCUUUGAAGGUGUACUCAAUGUGAUAAAGUCAGAUGAAGCUGUGGAAUCCAAGCCUGAGUUUAUUCUGACCUUUACGUAAUUAUACCUGUGAUCCUCUCAGCCCACUGUGAUCUAGAUUCUGUUCUCUCUCCACUUCUCUAAGACACACUGAGAAAUGUCCAUGACCAUUUUCUGUUGCUCUUAGAUAGAUAGCUGACCUAGGCAUGUCAAGGGAAGCACUCUCAGACCGGGCUCCAUCUCUGUGCACCGGGGUCUGCUUCAACAGCUUGGAGUCUGAAUUUGUCAGUGAAUACAGAUUAACCACCCUCUCAUAAACUGAUGUACACAUAGUCUCAAAAAAGACAUGAGUAAGUGAUAAUAUCCAUUUGUUAAUUUGCAGUUAGGAGUGAACCCUUUCAGAGACAUAAAUGCUUAAAUGGGCUAGUCAGGGUAUCCCCUUAUUGACAUGGAGGUAACAUUGAUGUUACGUUGGUCUUCCAGAGGCUGCUUCAUGAGAAUAGAAUCAGAGCAAUCGACAGUGGAUAGUAUUGUGGCUCUUUGGGAGGACAUUCAGUUGAUGCUGACUGACUGCAAUCCUUUGAGACAAGAUUUGGAUAUCUAUACUCUGCAACUUCCAGAAAAAACAUGUUUGAGGAGACCCGGUGAGCCUCCAUUGAUAAAAGGUUGGCUUCCUUAUCUUGGAGUGGUCCUGAACUUACGAAAAGACCCCUUAAGGUUCAUGAAAACACUUCAAAAGCAACAUGGUGACACUUUCACAGUUCUUCUUGGUGGAAAGUACAUAACAUUUAUCCUGGACCCCUUCCAGUACCAGCUAGUGAUAAAAAAUCAUAAACAAUUAAGCUUUCGAGUAUUUUCUAAUAAAUUAUUAGAGAAAGCAUUUAGCAUCAGUCAGUUGCAAAAAAAUCAUGACAUGAAUGAUGAGCUUCACCUCUGCUAUCAAUUUUUGCAAGGCAAAUCUUUGGACAUACUCUUGGAAAGCAUGAUGCAGAAUCUAAAACAAGUUUUUGAACCCCAGCUGUUAAAAACCACAAGUUGGGACACGGCAGAACUGUAUCCAUUCUGCAGCUCAAUAAUAUUUGAGAUCACAUUUACAACUAUAUAUGGAAAAGUUAUUGUUUGUGACAACAACAAAUUUAUUAGUGAGCUAAGAGAUGAUUUUUUAAAAUUUGAUGACAAGUUUGCAUAUUUAGUAUCCAACAUACCCAUUGAGCUUCUAGGAAAUGUCAAGUCUAUUAGAGAGAAAAUUAUAAAAUGCUUCUCAUCAGAAAAGUUAGCCAAGAUGCAAGGAUGGUCAGAAGUUUUUCAAAGCAGGCAAGAUGUCCUGGAGAAAUAUUAUGUGCACGAGGACCUUGAAAUAGGAGCACAUCAUUUAGGCUUUCUCUGGGCCUCUGUGGCAAACACUAUUCCAACUAUGUUCUGGGCAAUGUAUUAUCUUCUGCGGCACCCAGAAGCUAUGGCAGCAGUGCGUGACGAAAUUGACCGUUUGCUGCAGUCAACAGGUCAAAAGAAAGGGUCUGGAUUUCCCAUCCACCUCACCAGAGAACAAUUGGACAGCCUAAUCUGCCUAGAAAGCAGCAUUUUUGAAGCUUUACGACUGUCCUCAUAUUCAACCACCAUUCGUUUUGUUGAGGAGGAUUUGACUCUCAGUUCAGAGACCGGGGACUACUGUGUGCGAAAGGGAGACUUGGUAGCCAUCUUUCCUCCAGUCCUACAUGGUGACCCUGAAAUCUUUGAAGCUCCAGAGGAGUUUAGAUAUGAUCGUUUUAUAGAAGAUGGUAAGAAGAAAACCACCUUUUUCAAAAGAGGGAAAAAGCUGAAGUGUUACCUAAUGCCGUUUGGAACUGGAACCAGCAAAUGUCCAGGCCGAUUUUUUGCACUUAUGGAAAUAAAACAAUUGUUGGUUAUACUUUUAACUUAUUUUGAUUUAGAAAUAAUUGAUGAUAAGCCCAUAGGACUAAACUACAGCCGCUUGUUGUUUGGUAUUCAGUAUCCAGAUUCUGAUGUUUUAUUUAGAUACAAAGUGAAAUCUUAGAGAAGCUAAAAGGAAAGAAAAUAAAUCUAUCAAAAUUACCCUAAACAUCCUAAGCUCAUCUAUUUCUUUUUAAUUUCUGCAAAUGUAAUUGAUUUAUUUGUUUAAAAAGCGCUAAUUUCUAUUUGAUCUGAUAUCAGUCCAGUUUGUCCUUAGUCACAAAGCCCAUCAUAAUAUAAAACAGGAUGGUGGCAGGAAAAUGGACAUCAAAAUCAACUUAAGGGUAGGCUCAAAACAGGGUUGUUGUUGUUUUUUUAGUUUCUCCUUGUUGUGAUUUUCACCUGUUAUAAUAAAUGUACCUUCACACCAAUAGAUUGGGCACUGUGGAAUUUAAAUCACUCAAAUUGUUCUCUAAUAUGUAAAAUUACACUUUGAACUACUAGAAAAUUGUGCUGGAAAUGGACACAGUCUAACAAAUUCCAAAUUCUCACAGAAGAAGGAAAUUGAAUUUCCAUGAGUUACACUGGAUGAAAAUGUUCCCUUCAAGUAUAAUAUUAAUAAUACCUAUAUUUCCAGGGUAUGUGUGCAUUAAAUGAGUUUCACAGUAGAUUGAAUGCUUCAACUUCACUUCAAUAUUUAAUCAUGCAUAAAUGUUCCUUAUUACUUUGUAUACUAUGGCUCAAUAGAACAAAAUUUCUGGUUACAUAAGACCUUUCAUGUUCAAGUUAGAUACUGAUAAGAUUUAAUGUAUAAGAAAACACAGAACCUAUUAUAUAUUCAGAAAUUGCCCUAGACAUUAGUAUUAGGUUUAUUAUGGGAGCAAAUGUUGAAAUAAUUACAGCAUUGAUUAUAUCAUUUGGCUUUAGUAUAAACUAUACAGGUUAUGCAAAUAUUGCAAUUAACCCUUUCCUAAAUGCUUUCAUAUAUAUAAACUGAGAAGCUAGAUAUAGUAUUUGGUUUUGAUGUCUCACCUUUUGGAUUUGGAGUUCAUGUGUUCUAUUUUGAAUUACAACAUCAUGUAAUGCAGUGUAAUUUCAUAUGACACAUGCAGCAUUGUGUCAAUAAUUCAAAGAUUUUUUUUCAAUUGAGAGAGUAUCUGGCUGUGUUGCCCAGGCUGGUCUCAAAUCCUGACCUCAAGUGAUCCUCCCGCUUUGGUCCCUUGGGAACCUGGACUACAGGCAUGUACCACCAAGCCCAGUGAUUCAAAGAUUCUAAUAUCAGAGUACCACAUGAUUGGCAUCUGAUAUAAAUGAUGAUGCAAUAUAUAAGCAGGCAAGGCAGGUAAUAAAGUCCAGUUAAUUCAUGCUUCGUUAAUUGGAACUUCUAAUAUUUCAGAAAUCUGCUACUGUUUUGAGAAAAGGAAACUGACUUUAAAAAUAACAUUACAAAAUAUUUACAUUCUUAGUAAGUAAAUAAGACAGUCUAGCAUUUAUUUUAUCCUUCCUGAAGUACAUGUUCUGAAUGUUCCUUCAGUGAAGGUCUGCUGGUGCAAAUUCUAUUUUUGCUUGAUUUAGGGUGUCUUUAUUUUUACUCUCCUUCUUGAAAGAUGGUUUUGCUGGAUGCACAAAUCUAGAUUGACAGUUAUUUCCUCACAGCACUUUGAAGAUAUUGCCCGUUCUUAAGGUAUCCAUUGUUGUUAUUGGGCGGAUAGCCGUUAGUGAGUUUAAUUACUCAAUAGGUAGUCUGUCUCUUCUCUCUGACUACUUUAACGUGUCCUCUUUGUCUUUGAUGUUCUUAGUUUCUUUCUGUUUCUCAUGCUUGCAUGUCCUGCUGCUUCUUGAAUCUGAGCACAGGUGUCUCCCAUCAAGUAUGGAAUCUUCUCAGCCAUUCUCUCUGUGAAUAUUACUGUUCUCACACUCUACAUUAGAUCCUCUCACUCUACAUACAUCCUUUGAUCUUUUCUCACCACACUUUGUAUCUCUAACUUACACUCCAUGUAAUUUCUUUAGAUGUCUCUUCCAGUUUCUUCUUUGAACAGUAUAUCUAAUCUCUCCAACUCAUCCACUGAGUUUGUUUUUUCCUUCUUUUUGUUUUAACUCUAGGUUCAUCGAGUUGAGUGAUCACUCUCCUUACACUCUUUAGUUCAUGAUACACAAUUAUAAUUGGUUCUAAUAAGGUCCCUCUGGCUUUAUUUACUUAUUCUGUUUUGUCCCUAAUACCCACUUUCAUACCCCUUCCUAAUAUCAUAGGCAAAUAUUCUAAUGUGUUUGAUGCAUAUCUUGGUAUGUAUAUGUUUUCAUGUAACAUAUAUUAUCUUGAGUACCUAUUUUCUGUAAGUUAUAUUCUUCCUAAUUUUCUUAUGAAGCUCUGUGAUUUUAAAGAUAUAUUCAUAUUUCUGUAGUAUAUACAUAGUAUACUACUAUAUUUAAUCUAUUGCUUCUAACUGCUGCACAGCAAUCCAUAAUGUGCACACAUUAUGUUUUAAUGAUCUAGUUACCCAGUGAUGGACACUGUCAGCAGGACAGUUAUUGUGGGACAGAGGCCAAAGCAGAACUUAAAAGCUUUUCCAUCACCUAUCCUCACACUACUGUGCCUAACCAUCUCAGCCCAGGGCUGCUAAAUGCCUUGUCCCCAAGCCCCACCACCCACCCCCCACAUACACACAUUUAGUCCAUGAUAACUUUAAUUCUUCCUAAGAUGUUCUAAAUUUGUUAUGUCCCAUCCUCAGAUCCAUCCAAUCCUCUCCAUUCUGUAGGGUCUCCAAGGUUGAUUUUGAGUCAGAGUGUCAGUCUCCAGCUUGUUAACCUUCAGGUUUUCCAUUCCACUGAGUUUGCUAAGUUCAAUCAUUACAUUUUUCAGUUUUACGAUUCCCUUUUGUUCUUCAUAUAUGCUGCUUAUUUUUUAUAAUAUCUUGUACCUUUAUUAUAAACUCAACAUCCUUUUUCAUUUCUUCAACUGUAUGAAGCAAACAUUUUAGAUUCUGUAUCUGAUAUUUCCAAAUCAUUGGUGUUUUGUGGAUCUAAUUCUGUAGUUUAUGUGUUUUGCUGUCACUGUUACCAGGAAUGGCUUGUUUACUGAGCCCAUGUUCCUUGGAUUUUUAUCUCUGAAAAAUCUUUAGACCUAGAUUUAAAGUUCAUUCCUCAAGAGAGAAUUUGUAUUUGCAUUUUUCAGACUGCUGAUACUACUACCAAACUCAGAUCACCUUAAAAUUUCAGCUUGAUUAUCUGGGAGUGGGGAGGGAACGCUACAUAGGUAUUGUGGUUUCUAGCCCUAAAUCAGGUAGAAUGCAACCAUUUUAUUAGGAAUAGACAGGGGACACAUUUGGGGGUUCAUUUUUUUGUUUAUUUUUACCCGGAGCUAAGACUGAGAUAGGCAAAUAUACUGACAGUUUUGCUCUGUGGAGCACAGUUUCUUUCUAGUUCACCUAUUGAGUAUGUUGUCUUUGCAAGUUCUUGGCUUUAUGCAAAGGCCUUGGAUUACACACACACACACACACACACACACACACACACACACACACACACACACACACCCUGGGCCCUAGCCUUUAGUCCACCACAAAGCAUACUCUGUCCUUUUCGUACUUGGACGUCUAGUUCGCCAUGUUGCCUAAAGUGGAAGUUCCAUAGCUUUAAAUUCAACUUAGUGGUACACUUUUGUGAUGUUAAGGCACAGAGAACACAGGAAAUUAUUCCAUUCCAAUUUCGGCUUAUUUUAUAACUGGAAAUGUGUACAGGAAUUUAGAAAUGGAAAGUAAGGAUAAAUGAAAUGGUUGAGAAAAGAUGACAUAAAAGGAAUGAAUAGUAGAACCAAAACAAAACAUUGAGAAUCUUGUGACAGUCUUAAAUCCAGUAACUAAAUAGUAUUUACAAAUAGAAAAACAUGUCCUGGACAAAUCAGUUAAAAGAUGCAGAUUCUGGCUGUGACAUAACUGGCUUAUUAUUAAACAAUUUCCGUCUCAGAGCUUCAACGUCCUCAUUUGAAAAAUAAAAUAAUAAGGCCCUUUGACAUCAGAGUUCAUUGUAACGAUUAAACACAGUAACGUGUAUGGAUUUAUGGUAUAAUGCAAUAUACCAAUGCAAAGUUUAAUGAAGAUACUUCAACAGUGUUGUGCCUUUAAAAAAUUGCUCUUGUGUAUUGUUCAAGGGAAUCGUUUUUUAUAGUCAUUUGUUAAUUCAUUGUUCAUUUAUUCAACCAAACAUUCAUUGAGCAUUUUCUCUGUUCUAGAUAUGAUUGAUGCUAGACACUGGAUUCCCCUUCCCCUUCAAGAACAUACUAUUUGUUAGGGAAAACAAUACGUAGGCAACUAAUUUAUUAUAAAUGCAGUUGUAAGUGAUAAAUUCAUCUCUUUAAAACUAUUUUAAAAUUCUGAUUUAUCACUAGUUCUAACUAGCCUUCCAUCAGUCAUUCCAAAGUAAUGGUCUGUAAUGAGAAAUCACUAUGUAUAAUUAUACACAAUAAAAAUAUAUACAACAGGUAUUUUGAUAAUAUGAUAAUUAAAACCAAAUAUAGUCAUUGAGGCUUAGAAUUUUUAAAAACUGUAUUAUAUAUUGUAAAAUCCCAUCCUUUUUUUUUUUUAGAUGGAGUCUUGCUCUGUCGCCCAGGCUGGAGUCCAGUGGCAUGAUCUCAGCUCACUGCAACCUCCACUUCCUGGGUUCAAGCAAUUCCCUUGUCUCAGCCCUCCGAGUAGCUGGGACUACAGGCACCCACCACUAUGCCUGACCAACUUUUGUAUUUUUAGUGGAGACGAGGUUUCACCAUGUUGAUCAGGCUGGUCUCGAACUCCAGACCUCAGGUGAUCCACCCGCCUCGGACUCCCUAAGUGCUGGGGUUGCAGACAUGAGCCACCGUGCCCGCCCCCAUCUUUUCAUUUUUAUAGCUUCACCUAAGUUUUGAAUUAAAAGAAAUAAAUAAUUAAUACCCAAAAUAUUGUUUUAUAUCAAUGACCAACGUAAUGAAACACUCAGCAGAAACUAAAGCCCUGAAGUGGUUAAGAAAAAGCUACCUAUCACUAAAUCAGGCAUGCUUAUAAGCAACCUAGAAGAAAACUUUUAUCUGCCUUGUUUUGGCUUUCCUGGCAUACUUCCUUACUUCAUCUCCAUUUUAUAAUUAAGUUUUGGGUCACAAGUCUAAGGCAAAGGAGCUUCCAUACUGAAAAUCUACAUUUUUAAUGCUUAUUUUAUCAUAAAAAUAAUUUGGGUAAUUUUCUGCAAGUGACUUCUAACUUAACAGUAGAAGUUUAAAACUGUUCAAAGACCAAAGCACAACAUUUAUCUAGUGUUUGAUCCUAGUAUAAAAGAAUGGCAAUAAUUAUGUGAACAGGAAUUACAUGCCCUUAGAAUGUGCAUUUUUUAACCUAUUAAAUUUGCCAAUCUUGCAAACUAUUGUUUACUUGUAUUGCAUAAUUAGAUACUCAUAUUAACAUAUUGAAUUCAGAAAAAGUUAGCAAGCCAAGAUGACAUUCUCUGUAGCACUAUUUUAAAUUAUAAUGAAUGAUCACAUAAAACUCUUUAGUAUUUAUCUAAAGUAAUUAUUACUCUACUUCAUUUGUUUAUCUAAAUCAGUGAUCAUUGAUGUUUGAACUUUUUGGCUUAAAUGUUUAUUUUGUUUAUACUACUUGCUAGAGUAAAAUAAAUUUAAUACAUGAAAAACUCUACACAAUUUAAAAUAGGUUAUAAUUUGUCAAUACUUAUGUUUUAAAAUAUUUUUAGAAGGAGGAGUGCUGUAUAUUAUUAAAACAAUUUUCUGAAAUUGUUUAAUAUUAUCUUUGAUUUUAAAAUGACAUAUAUGUGGAUUUACAAUGAAUCAAAUUGUCCUAAAAGAUGUCAGAUAAGAAAUGCAAGUGCUUUGCAAGUCUAAUACUUAAUGUUCUUUUAUGUACAACAAAAAUUUAAUAAAUUAACUUUAAAGCACA